GGGGAGGAGCCAAGAUGGCUGAAUAGGAACAGCUCCGGUCUACAGCUCCCAGAGUGAGCAACGCAGAAGAUGGGUGAUUUCUGCAUUUCCAGUCGAGGUACCGGGUUCAUCUCACUAGGGAGUGCCAGACACUGGGCGCAGGGCUGAAAAAGCACGAGUGUCCGCACUAUGACAAAAGAAAAGCGGCGUCUCCUCAAAACACCACCAUGUUCCCCUAUGAGUCUGGUGAGCCAAGACACUAAGAAACUGCAGGAAACGAGAGAGUUCUCGGGGUGGGGGUGUCCAUGGAUGAAGCACCGAACAAACUGGAGCCCGCAAGAGUCUUGCCUUCUUUUGAGCCUAAGUCAUGAGUUGGAUGUUCCUCAGAGAUCUCCUGAGUGGAGUAAAUAAAUACUCCACUGGGACUGGAUGGAUUUGGCUGGCUGUCGUGUUUGUCUUCCGUUUGCUGGUCUACAUGGUGGCAGCAGAGCACGUGUGGAAAGAUGAGCAGAAAGAGUUUGAGUGCAACAGUAGACAGCCCGGUUGCAAAAAUGUGUGUUUUGAUGACUUCUUCCCCAUUUCCCAAGUCAGACUUUGGGCCUUACAACUGAUAAUGGUCUCCACACCUUCACUUCUGGUGGUUUUACAUGUAGCCUAUCAUGAGGGUAGAGAGAAAAGGCACAGAAAGAAACUCUAUGUCAGCCCAGGUACAAUGGAUGGGGGCCUAUGGUACGCUUAUCUUAUCAGCCUCAUUGUUAAAACUGGUUUUGAAAUUGGCUUCCUUGUUUUAUUUUAUAAGCUAUAUGAUGGCUUUAGUGUUCCCUACCUUAUAAAGUGUGAUUUGAAGCCUUGUCCCAACACUGUGGACUGCUUCAUCUCCAAACCCACUGAGAAGACGAUCUUCAUCCUCUUCUUGGUCAUCACCUCAUGCUUGUGUAUUGUGUUGAAUUUCAUUGAACUGAGUUUUUUGGUUCUCAAGUGCUUUAUUAAGUGCUGUCUCCAAAAAUAUUUAAAAAAACCUCAAGUCCUCAGUGUGUGAGUGCCACAGCCUCAGAUAUGUUGAAUGUGGUAGGAGAGGGACCCCUCCCCUACUCCAGAAUCUUCACACUUGGCCAUAAACACACUCCCUCUACCUGAAGCAAAGCUACUCUGUGACACACAAGAGGGUUAAACAAAGAAAACCUGCAUCCCUCCUCAGCAAGGCCUAAGCUGAGUUGGAAGACAAAGCACAUCAGCCUUAGUAUCAUUUGGGAGGAAUUUUUUUACAUUGUCAAUAUGCUUUCAGUUAUGAGCUCUAGACAGAGGUCUCAUUGUUUUGUUGUAGGGUUCUCCAGUAUGUGGAUAACAUUAGUUGUUUUAGAAUAGGUAAUUGCAAAUUAGUCUGAAGAAAUCUAACAGGAUUCUUUUAAGAGCUUAGAUUUUUCAGGGAAAAAAAAAAAAAAAGAAACCCUGUGUCAGUUUUCUGUUUUUUCUAACUAUCUCAUUACAAUUGGUGCACAAUGAACUGGAAAAUAUAAAAAGUGACACUUUAGGCAAAUGUGAUGGCCUCCGAGCUGAAAUGAAGGAACUGGCAAUCUUUCCAAAGUGGCAGCCAAGGCCCCACUCCCUGUCCUACUCAAUCUCUGCAGGGAAAAACUGUGGGAUAGGAUAGCAGCCAGCUGGGGACACACAGAGGAACAUUCAACAGGAAGGUCCCGCCUAGGGAAAAGGCCACAGAGCCCAGGCCUCUUGCCGAUUCAGGGAUCCUUGGAUAUAAGUGGAUUAGAGGAGAGGGAGGAAAGCUAUCAUUUCAGUGGUCUCCAAAUCAAGUAGAAAUAUUACUGGGAGGUAUCCCACUUAAGCCUGAACCAGCAGACAUCCGAAAGGGUCACUCUAGAGUCAGAAAGGAAAGCAGGUCCCCCAGAAGGCAACACAUUGAUAGGAAGUGGAGGCCACAGAAAAAGAAUGUGCCCACUUGAUAAUUACUUAAGACUUCUAUUUAACCAAAAGAACAUUGAAAUACUUUGUAAAUAUUCAUAUUGUUGAACCUUUCAUAAUCAGGAAUUCACUAUGUACUAUACUGUAAGUCAUAGUUCGCCUAUAAUUUACUAGUAUAUCUCCCUCUAGGACAGAUAGUAAAAUGUGUACUAUGUUGUUACAGUGGUGCAAAAAUGUUUUAAAAGUUUAUCACUUGUUUUGAAGACUAGAACUUUCUUUACUUUUCUAUAUUUUCUUAGCAAUUCACAGAUAUGUUCUCUUUGGAUUUAGUACUUUAACAUAUGUACAUUUCUUCAGAAUAAAAAUAAGGGUAUUUCACAAUG